GUCAUCGGCCAGGUCACAGAGUCUCACUUCAGGACAGCUGUGCAAGCAGAACCCCCAUCACGGUUUUCUUGAUGCCUUUGACAGUCACCUGUACAUGCCUCUGGGACCUUUCCUCCUCCUUUCUCUUUUUGUUUUUUUUCCCUUGGUCACAUGUUUCAUUCUACUAAAUGUCUAACCAGCUCUUCUCUGUAAAUUACAGAGCUGUGAUGGCACCUUGCUUGUUGAUUAUUUCUGGUUGAAUAGUUUCCAAUGGGACUUCUCUGGAGAUAAGUCCUGUAUUAGUCCGUUCUCACACUGCUAAUAAAAACAUACCUGAGACUGGGUAAUUUAUAAAGGAAAGAGGUUGACUCACAGUUCAGCAUGGCUGGGGAGACCUCAGGAAACUUACAAUCGUGGUGGAAGGGGAAGCAAACAUGUCCUUCACAUGGCAGCAGGAGAGAGAAGUGCCGAGCAAAAGGGGGGAAAGCCCUUUAUAAAACCAUCAGAUCUCAUGAGAACUAACUCACUAUCAUGAGAACAGGAUGGGGGAAACUGCCCCCAUGAUUAAAUUAUCUCUGCCUGGUCCCUCCCAUGACAUGGGGAUUAUGAGAACUACAAUUCAAGAUGAGAAUUGGUGGUGACAUAGCCAAACCACAUUAAAUCCCAAGUGCGCAUGUCUGGCCCUGAUCCCUUUAUGUGAGACUGGGGUCAUGAUCCUCCCGCACCCGUCUUCUGAGCCCUAUUCCUACUUGGGCAUGCUUAGGCACUUCAGCAUCUGCAUCCCAUUGAUGUCUUAAGGGUGGUUCCAGACCUUGGAGGUACACACGACACACUGCUGAUGAAAACCUAGAAUAUAGAAUGGAAGUUACAUUUAUUCAUAGAGUGAAAAUCCAAAAAUAGACCAGAGAGAAGAUAUGAAAAUAUCAAGAAUGCUUAUCUUAGGGAGGUAGGAUUAUAGGUAACUUUUUUUUUCCUUAGAUAAAUAUAUAGAUAGAUAUAUUAGUGUUUACAGUUUCUCUGCCACCAACCAAAAUAUUUUUUUCAGGAGGAAAAAAAACCCCAGCCAGCCAACAUACCUAAAAACCAUCUCCUGGGCCCGAGAGGGAAAAAUUGGGCUCCUUUUCUUGAAAUUGCCAUUUGUGCCACUGUUGUAUUAUUUUACCAGUAACUCCAGAUUCCAGGCUCCUGUAUCUGAGUUCUCUCUCCUUCCACAGUGGAGCUCAUACCUUCCUGUUUCCUGGCUGCCACUCAGAUUUAGGCUCCGUUUUUCAGACCUCAGUGGCUGUAAUAGCUGUUCCUUCUACCUCUUAGGAUGGUUCUUUCUGUAAUAGCCUUUGUCAUCACAUCAUCAGAGGAUGAUAGCUCUUAAUGAGGAUCUAAAAUUUGCAGGUAAGAUAUCCCUGCCUCUGACAUGAGAUAGAUGUAUUGCAUGCUAUUUAACAUACAACUAUACUGAGUGUGCAGUUGUAUGUAAAAGCAUUGUUCUAGGUAUUGGGUUGAAAGUGGAUCAAAUGCUAGACAAAGGAGCGUACAAGUCUUGUAAGGAAGACAGCUGCCAAGAGAGAAGAAAGGAUGGGGAAAUGCUGCGUCUACUAAGUUCAAGGUUCUGAAUUGGAAAGCUGCAGCUAUUGAGGAGAAGAGUCUUUUAAAAUUCCUAAAGGGUUUUUGUUAUCUUUUAUUGAUGCAAAUGCUAUUUUGUGGCAUAAACCUUAAUAAUUUUGGGGUUGAAACUCUUAUCAGGAUAAAAUGAUCCUUUUCUAUCCCAAGCUUAAUAAAUAUUGUUUAAGUACAAAUUAAAUAUAUGAAAUCUGCCCAUCUAUAUUAUAAAUGUCAUAUGGCAGAAAUUAUACCUUGACUUUUGGUUCUUUCACAAAACCUUAAUUUUUUUUUUUUUUUUUUGCCUUCAAUGAAUUUUGUCUGAUUUUACAUUAAAAGCCUGUAAUUUCUCAAGUCUUGAGUCUGGGGAGCCGUCGUCAUCCUUUUUUCCCCUCUCCCUUGUCUUCUGGAUGUUCAAGCGAUUUUAAUUAGAUGUUGGGCUUUUAUGUCAAGUGCUGGCAUUGCACUCCAUGAUAAUCCAGGGACUCGGAAGCACAUGUUAUGCGUCACCCUGGGUUGGUGCAGUGGAACUGGGGUGGGUUGGAAGUAGUAUUCUAAAUCUGCUUCCUGCGAUGGGGUAGGUCAGGUUGUCCUGUGUUGACAAGGAAGAAGUCUGGGUGAGGAAGCGGGAUGAAAGCAGACCAGACGCUAGAGUCCACUUUCAAGUCCGAUCCCAGGACCUGGCUUAAAGUUAAAGAACAGCAAAGAUGAAAGGUGCCGCACAGCAGCACAGGUCGGUGGCCACGUUAAUGACAUAGAAAGCAAGUGCUGUGAAUUCAAAAGAAAGGACAGCUCUGAGCCAGAGUACUUGGUGACUUUGCUCAAACAAAUCCCUUUCUGGCACCCCCAGGCCUUCCCUCCCGCUUCAAAAAAAUUCUGAAUUGUGCCAAUCCAUUGAGGCUCAGCUCAAGGCCAUCCCAUGCCUUUCCAUCGUAAUAAAGCCUUGUUUCCUGGGCUUUAAACAUAUUCCUUUUUUCUUAGGUACAGAUUGAACUUUUUUAAAAGGGAAGUUGUCAGAGGCUCUGUAAAACGUUAAAUCAAACCUGCUUUGUUUUAGGGAUGGGGUAGCUUGGAAUCAGAUUUGCUCCUGCUAUGGACUGAACAUUUGUGUCCCCCCAAAAUUCCUAUGUUGAAGCCCUAAUGCACAGUGUUAUGGUGUUUGAAGGGAGGCCCUUGGGAGGUGAUUAAGUUUAGAUGAGAUUGUGUGAGUGAAGCCCUCAUGAAUGGGAUUACUGUCAUCCCAAAAAGAGGUAGAGACCCCAGAGCUUCCUCUCUCUUCACCCUGUGAGGAUACAGCAAGAAGGAAGCUCUCUGCAAGUCAGGAAGAGAGAGGGCUCUCACUAGAAUACACUUGUACUGCCACCCUGAUCUUGGACUUCCCCUCCAGAACUGUGAGAAACAAAUGUGUGUUGUUUAAGCCACCCAGUCCCUAUGAUUUUAUUAGAGCAGCCCGAGCUCCAUUCUCCACUCCCUGGCUUCCUGCAUGGACUUUGCAACCAGAGCUUCACGGGAUUAUUCAGAGCUGGGAGAGCUUCCCCCACGAUCUCCUUUAGAACCAGUUUGUGAAGAUGGGCCCUUUGGCCCCCCACCAGAGGAAAAGAAAAGGACAUCUCGUGAGCUCCGAGAGCUGUGGCAAAAGGCUAUUCUUCAACAGAUACUGCUGCUUAGAAUGGAGAAGGAAAAUCAGAAGCUCCAAGCCUCUGAAAAUGAUUUGCUGAACAAGCGCCUGAAGCUCGAUUAUGAAGAAAUUACUCCCUGUCUUAAAGAAGUAACUACAGUGUGGGAAAAGAUGCUUAGCACUCCAGGAAGAUCAAAAAUUAAGUUUGACAUGGAAAAAAUGCACUCGGCUGUUGGGCAAGGUGUGCCACGUCAUCACCGAGGUGAAAUCUGGAAAUUUCUAGCUGAGCAAUUCCACCUUAAACACCAGUUUCCCAGCAAACAGCAGCCAAAGGAUGUGCCAUACAAAGAACUCUUAAAGCAGCUGACUUCCCAGCAGCAUGCGAUUCUUAUUGACCUUGGGCGAACCUUUCCUACACACCCAUACUUCUCUGCCCAGCUUGGAGCAGGACAGCUAUCGCUUUACAACAUUUUGAAGGCCUACUCACUUCUAGACCAGGAAGUGGGAUAUUGCCAAGGUCUCAGCUUUGUAGCAGGCAUUUUGCUUCUUCAUAUGAGUGAGGAAGAGGCGUUUAAAAUGCUCAAGUUUCUGAUGUUUGACAUGGGGCUGCGGAAACAGUAUCGGCCAGACAUGAUUAUUUUACAGAUCCAGAUGUACCAGCUCUCGAGGUUGCUUCAUGAUUACCACAGAGACCUCUACAAUCACCUGGAGGAGCACGAGAUCGGCCCCAGCCUCUACGCUGCCCCCUGGUUCCUCACCAUGUUUGCCUCACAGUUCCCGCUGGGAUUCGUAGCCAGAGUCUUUGAUAUGAUUUUUCUUCAGGGAACAGAGGUCAUAUUUAAAGUGGCUUUAAGUCUGUUGGGAAGCCAUAAGCCCUUGAUUCUGCAGCAUGAAAACCUAGAAACCAUAGUUGACUUUAUAAAAAGCACGCUACCCAACCUUGGCUUGGUACAGAUGGAAAAGACCAUCAAUCAGGUAUUUGAAAUGGACAUCGCUAAACAGUUACAAGCUUAUGAAGUUGAGUACCACGUCCUUCAAGAAGAACUUAUCGAUUCCUCUCCUCUCAGUGACAACCAAAGAAUGGAUAAAUUAGAGAAAACCAACAGCAGCUUACGCAAACAGAACCUUGACCUCCUUGAACAGUUGCAGGUGGCAAAUGGUAGGAUCCAAAGCCUUGAGGCCACCAUUGAGAAGCUCCUGAGCAGUGAGAGCAAGCUGAAGCAGGCCAUGCUUACCUUAGAACUGGAGCGGUCGGCCCUGCUGCAGACGGUGGAGGAGCUGCGGCGGCGGAGCGCAGAGCCCAGCGACCGGGAGCCUGAGUGCACGCAGCCCGAGCCCACGGGCGACUGACAGCUCUGCAGGAGAGAUUGCAACACCAUCCCACACUGUCCAGGCCUUAACUGAGAGGGACAGAAGACGCUGGAAGGAGAGAAGGAAGCGGGAAGUGUGCUUCUCAGGGAGGAAACCGGCUUGCCAGCAAGUAGAUUCUUACGAACUCCAACUUGCAAUUCAGGGGGCAUGUCCCAGUGUUUUUUUUGUUGUUUUUAGAUACUAAAUCGUCCCUUCUCCAGUCCUGAUUACUGUACACAGUAGCUUUAGAUGGCGUGGACGUGAAUAAAUGCAACUUAUGUUUUCUUGUUGGUUCCUUUUUGAGUGUCACUGUGUUUGUAAAGAGCAUUCACAAUACGGUGGAAUUUCAAAAGCUGGAAGAGCUCGAGAUCAUGCCUCAGGCAAAGGCGUGGGUCCAUCGUUCUUCCGAGAGGGUUUGUGUGGCGACUACACCCUCAGCGUCCCUGGCAAGGUGCAGUUGGCUCUCGCCCAUUCUUGUUAUGGAAACCUAAGAUGAUCAUUGGGAAGAUCAGUGAUCUUGGGUCAUUGAUCCCUGGCUCAGAGGAUAGCGGUUUCCAUCAUAAACCAAGAUGAUGAGUUCAGCCUUUAUCCCUCGUGGUUCCACUAGAUGUAACUUAAAGGAGUUAACAUUUGAGGACUUUGUUCUACAUCAGAUUUUACUAUUUGAAUGUUUAAGAUCACUUUAUUGAAUUUGAAGAUCAUCAAAUUAAAUAAAAUGAUUUAUUUAAUUUGGAUAUCCUGAUCACUGUCAAGUGAAAUGGAUCUCUCUCUUUGGUAUUUAAGGAAGUUUGUCUUUAAAAAAAAAAUAGAGUGUUUUCAUACAUUUUUGCUUAUCCCAUAAGUACAGUUGAUCAAAGUCAUAGUAGGUAAAUGCUUUAUGGGACAGCUGACACCUUUUAGACCCUACCAGGUAUUGCUAGCAUGUGAGCUGCAGUUGUGGGGUCUGAGAUAUUUCUUUGUGGUAGUUUCAUACCCAUACUAUAGAGUCAUGUAUUUAUUUUUGCCUGUUGUGUGAUGUAAUGCAAUCAUGUUCCUUUGAGUCUCCAUCCCUUGGAAAUCUGACUUCUUGCAGAAGGAGUAGGCACAUCAAGAUAUUCAGGGGUGCCCCAAGAGUCUGGGACUUUCAAAAAAAAAAGAUCAGGCUGAAACUGCAGUCAGAUUUAUGACAGCUGACAGUUUUUCAGAGGUCGCACACAGUGACUCUCCUCUCUCAGGAUGACGAGGACCUGUGCCUUCAACAAGCAAAAUGCUGCUCACGGUUGUCCUGCUUGCAGCCAGUCACUGUGUAAAGCCUCUCUGAUGUGCACUUAAGAGUGGGUUGCUUUCUCACAAAGAUGGGGUUCUGUGCAGUCACAGGUCACUUCCUUGACAACACAAUCAUUUCUGAUCUUUAUCACUGUAACCACGUCUUCUAUUCCAUAGGAGUUUCUUUUGAUUCUCUCAGUUGCGGGGGGCAUCUCUUAAUCCUGGGGUAAAAGGAGAGAUUGCCAUACUUAGACUCACUGUGAGUCUCCCCGGCCAUUUCACGAGGAGACCACAGUGCUGCCACCAGUGCCUAAACAGGUGGCUGGCAUUCGAGACUUCCUCCUGUUCCCUGGGUCAGAGGAUAGCGGUUUCCAUCAUAAACCAAGAUGAUGAGUUCAGCCUUUAUCCCUCGUGGUUCCGCUAGAUGUAACUUAUAGGAGUUAACAUUUGAGGACUUUGUUCUGCAUCAGAUCUUACUAUUUGAAUGUUUACUGUUGGAUUUUGGGCAUCUUAUUACUGUUACUCAAAAACAUUGACUCUGCAUCAAGAAAGAAACAAGAAAGCAAUAAAACAAGAAAUAAUUCAUGCUCACA